ACACAAUACCCAGGAGCUUGCCUUGCUCGGCUCUGGGGCCAUGCUGACAUGCUGACAUCGCCCCCUGAGGACUUGGCUGCAACCCCAGAGCCCCCAGGGUGUCCCGGAGCCCUGGACCGUGCUGGCAGCUGGACGGAGCUCCCUGGCUGAGCCAGCUGGGCAGAGAGAGGGCUUCCCCUGCCGGAACAGCCAAACAGCAUCAGCAGCGGGCCUGGGCCCAGAGAGGGCCAGGUGGGUGGCAGAGCAAAAGAGGAAUGGACUGUGGGCCACCUGCUACCCUCCAGCCCCACCUGACUGGGCCACCUGGCACUGCCCACCACCCUGUAGCAGUGUGCCAGCAGGAGAGUCUGUCCUUUGCAGAGCUGCCCGCCCUGAAGCCCCCGAGCCCAGUGUGUCUGGACCUUUUCCCUGUUGCCCCAGAGGAGCUUCGGGCUCCUGGCAGCCGCUGGUCCCUGGGGACCCCUGCCCCUCUCCAAGGGUUGCUAUGGCCAUUAUCCCCAGGAGGCUCAGAUACAGAGAUCACCAGCGGGGGGAUGCGGCCCAGCAGGGCUGGCAGCUGGCCACACUGUCCUGGUGCCCAGCCCCCAGCUCUGGAGGGACCCUGGAGUCCCCGACACACACAGCCACAGCGCCGGGCCAGCCACGGCUCGGAGAAGAAGUCUGCCUGGCGCAAGAUGCGGGUGUACCAGCGUGAAGAGGUCCCCGGCUGCCCCGAGGCCCACGCUGUCUUCCUAGAGCCUGGCCAGGUAGUGCAAGAGCAGGCCCUGAGCACAGAGGAGCCCAGGGUGGAGUUGUCUGGGUCCACCCGAGUGAGCCUCGAAGGUCCUGAGCGGAGGCGCUUCUCGGCAUCGGAGCUGAUGACCCGGCUGCACUCUUCUCUGCGCCUGGGGCGGAAUUCAGCAGCCCGGGCACUCAUCUCUGGGUCAGGCACCGGAGCAGCCCGGGAAGGGAAAGCAUCUGGAAUGGAGGCUCGAAGUGUAGAGAUGAGCGGGGACCGGGUGUCGCGGCCAGCCCCUGGUGACUCACGAGAGGGCGAUUGGUCCGAGCCCAGGCUAGACACACAGGAAGAGCCGCCUUUGGGGUCCAGGAGCACCAACGAGCGGCGCCAGUCUCGAUUCCUCCUUAACUCCGUCCUCUAUCAGGAAUACAGCGACGUGGCCAGCGCCCGCGAACUGCGGCGGCAGCAGCGCGAGGAGGAGGGCCCGGGGGACGAGGCCGAGGGCGCAGAGGAGGGGCCGGGGCCGCCGCGGGCCAACCUCUCCCCCAGCAGCUCCUUCCGGGCGCAGCGCUCGGCGCGAGGCUCCACCUUCUCGCUGUGGCAGGAUAUCCCCGACGUACGCGGCAGCGGCGUCCUGGCCACGCUGAGCCUGCGGGACUGCAAGCUGCAGGAGGCCAAGUUUGAGCUGAUCACCUCCGAGGCCUCCUACAUCCACAGCCUGUCGGUGGCUGUGGGCCACUUCUUAGGCUCUGCCGAGCUGAGCGAGUGUCUGGGGGCGCAGGACAAGCAGUGGCUGUUUUCCAAACUGCCCGAGGUCAAGAGCACCAGCGAGAGGUUCCUGCAGGACCUGGAGCAGCGGCUGGAGGCAGAUGUGCUGCGCUUCAGCGUGUGCGACGUGGUGCUGGACCACUGCCCGGCCUUCCGCAGAGUCUACCUGCCCUAUGUCACCAACCAGGCCUACCAGGAGCGCACCUACCAGCGCCUGCUCCUGGAGAACCCCAGGUUCCCUGGCAUCCUGGCUCGCCUGGAGGAGUCUCCUGUGUGCCAGCGUCUGCCCCUUACCUCCUUCCUUAUCCUGCCCUUCCAGAGGAUCACCCGCCUCAAGAUGUUGGUGGAGAACAUCCUGAAGCGGACAGCACAGGGCUCUGAAGACGAAGACAUGGCCACCAAGGCCUUCAAUGCGCUCAAGGAGCUGGUGCAGGAGUGCAAUGCUAGUGUACAGUCCAUGAAGAGGACAGAGGAACUCAUCCACCUGAGCAAGAAGAUCCACUUUGAGGGCAAGAUUUUCCCGCUGAUCUCUCAGGCCCGCUGGCUGGUUCGGCAUGGAGAGUUGGUAGAGCUGGCACCACUGCCUGCAGCACCCCCUGCCAAGCUGAAGCUGUCCAGCAAGGCAGUCUACCUCCACCUCUUCAAUGACUGCUUGCUGCUCUCUCGGCGGAAGGAGCUAGGGAAGUUUGCCGUUUUCGUCCAUGCCAAGAUGGCUGAGCUGCAGGUGCGGGACCUGAGCCUGAAGCUGCAGGGCAUCCCCGGCCACGUGUUCCUCCUCCAGCUCCUCCACGGGCAGCACAUGAAGCACCAGUUCCUGCUGCGGGCCCGGACGGAAAGUGAGAAGCAGCGAUGGAUCUCAGCCUUGUGCCCCUCCAGCCCCCAGGAGGACAAGGAGGUCAUCAGUGAGGGGGAAGAUUGCCCCCAGGUUCAGUGUGUUAGGACAUACAAGGCACUGCACCCAGAUGAGCUGACCUUGGAGAAGACUGACAUCCUGUCAGUGAGGACCUGGACCAGUGACGGCUGGCUGGAAGGGGUCCGCCUGGCAGAUGGUGAGAAGGGGUGGGUGCCCCAGGCCUAUGUGGAAGAGAUCAGCAGCCUCAGCGCCCGCCUCCGAAACCUCCGGGAGAAUAAGCGAGUCACAAGUGCCACCAGCAAACUGGGGGAGGCUCCUGUGUGAUGGGCAGCCAUGGCCUAGGACCCCACCUCCAUGCCUGGCUCCUGGAUGGUCCUGGAGGGGCCUGCAGUGUCUCCAUUCCCCAAGCUGCUCCUGCUGGCACUUCGCUUCUGUGGCCUUGGCAUUGAGGGCACAGGCUGGACACAGGAAUGGGGGCGCCUCCAGAGGGUCUCUCCGUCCUCAUGCUCCUCAGUGUCCACACUUCAAGGCCAAGGAUAGUUUCUUCCUCUGACAUGGGGACCAUAACAGGUGAUCACUGAUACCUGGCAAAGACUGGGGCCCUCUCCUUUCUAUGUCCUCAAUCCUGCCUGACUCUUGGUCCUUCUGGCAGGGACCUGGCUGGGGAACGUUCUGGUGCUGAUGGUGCUGGGACCUAUAUGUAUAUUUAUAUAUAUCUGGGGUCUUGUCUACCACCUCCCCUGGUCAGAGCCUGAGUGGGUGCUGGUUGCUGUGUCUUGUCUGUAAAUAAACUCCUAUCAUGCCUUUGCUUGGAGUCUGUGAUCCAUCUGAUGCUGCCCCCACCCCCACAGUCCUAUUUUCCCAGCUAAAGACCAGGAGAGUCUCCGGCUGGCUCCCAACUGGGGCUUUGCAUUUCUCUAGAGUUCAUCUCUGAGCUGUAAGGGUGACCAGGGGGCAGGGGGACGAUUGUGUAUCAGCUAGGCUGCUUUUGGCUGCAAGUAACAAAAUAUCAGAUACAAAUAGGCUUAAACAUUAAAGAGAUUUGAUUAGUUCUUUA